GGGCAGUGGGGCUGGGAGAUGGGGCGGGGCUGGGCGCUCCGGGACUGAGGUGCUGAUCGCCCAAAGGGCGCCCCUGGGCUGGGGUCUGACCCGGCUUCUCCUCCCUCACUACCCGCGGUCCCCGGCCUCUCGGCGCUGCGCUGUUACCUCAUCCGAAAAGUGUUCGCUGCAGCAUCCUCAGGCUUCACGUUGGAGCCUCUUGAUUGUGGUGUUCAGCAUUAUUUAAGAUCACCUAUGCAUCAUCUGAAGCCACAGUCCCAGGUCAUCUUCAUCACCUUCCCCAGUGGAAUGCCUCCUGUGUUAAAGCCCACAACAACCCCUGUGGAGGAACAACCAUGUCAUCAGAAUCGAGCAAAAAACGGAAGCCCAAAGUGAUCCGAAGCGAUGGAGCCCCAGCUGAAGGAAAGCGGAAUCGAUCUGACACCGAGCAGGAAGGUAAAUACUACAGUGAGGAGGCCGAGGUGGAUCUGCGGGACCCUGGCAGAGACUAUGAGUUAUACAAGUACACCUGCCAGGAGCUACAGAGGCUGAUGGCUGAGAUCCAAGACCUGAAGAGCAGGGGUGGCAAGGAUGUGGCAAUAGAAAUAGAAGAACGGAGGAUCCAGAGCUGUGUGCAUUUCAUGACUCUAAAGAAGCUUAACCGAUUAGCCCACAUCAGGUUGAAGAAAGGAAGAGAUCAGACCCACGAGGCUAAGCAGAAAGUAGAUGCCUAUCAUCUGCAGCUCCAGAACCUGUUGUAUGAGGUGAUGCACCUACAGAAGGAGAUCACCAAAUGUUUGGAGUUUAAGUCAAAGCAUGAAGAAAUUGAUCUGGUCAGUUUAGAGGAGUUUUAUAAGGAGGCUCCACCAGAUAUCAGCAAGGCCGAAGUCACCAUGGGAGACCCUCACCAGCAAACACUGGCACGUCUGGACUGGGAGCUGGAGCAGCGGAAAAGGCUGGCAGAGAAGUACCGAGAGUGCCUAUCUAACAAGGAGAAGAUUCUCAAGGAGAUUGAGGUGAAGAAGGAGUACCUGAGCAGCCUCCAGCCCCGCCUCAACAGCAUCAUGCAGGCUUCCCUUCCGGUGCAGGAGUACCUGUUUAUGCCAUUCGACCAGGCUCACAAGCAGUAUGAGACAGCCAGACACCUGCCGCCUCCCCUCUAUGUCCUCUUUGUUCAGGCCACUGCGUAUGGGCAGGCCUGUGCUCAUAUGAAAUCCUCCCAGCCCCCUAGACAGGAUAAGACGUUAUCUGUGGCAAUCGAAGGCAGUGUGGAUGAAGCCAAGGCUCUGUUCAAACCUCCAGAGGACUCCCAAGAUGACGAGAGUGACUCAGAUGCCGAGGAGGAGCAGACUACGAAGCGCCGGAGACCCACACUGGGGGUUCAGUUGGACGACAAACGCAAGGAGAUGCUGAAGAGGCACCCACUGUCUGUCAUGCUCGACCUGAAGUGCAAAGAUGACAGUGUGCUUCACCUGACUUUCUACUACCUCAUGAACCUCAACAUCAUGACAGUAAAAGCCAAAGUGACAACUGCCAUGGAGCUGAUCACCCCCAUCAGUGCAGGUGACUUGCUGUCUCCUGACUCAGUCCUGAGUUGCUUGUAUCCUGGGGAUCAUGGAAAGAAAACUCCGAAUCCAGCCAAUCAGUAUCAGUUUGAUAAAGUUGGCAUCCUGACUUUGAGCGACUAUGUACUUGAGCUAGGUCACCCCUAUUUGUGGGUGCAGAAGCUGGGUGGCCUCCACUUCCCCAAAGAGCAGCCCCAGCAAACAGUGAUUGCUGACCACUCGCUGAGCGCCAGCCACAUGGAGACCACCAUGAAACUUCUGAAGACCAGGGUGCAGUCCCGCCUGGCCCUCCACAAACAGUUUGCAUCCCUAGAACAUGGCAUUGUGCCAGUUACCAGUGAUUGCCAGUACCUCUUCCCUGCCAAGGUUGUCUCUCGCCUGGUGAAAUGGGUGACAGUUGCCCAUGAGGAUUACAUGGAGCUGCACUUCACCAAAGACAUUGUGGAUGCGGGACUGGCUGGGGACACCAAUCUCUACUACAUGGCGCUCAUCGAAAGGGGCACAGCCAAACUGCAGGCCGCUGUGGUGUUGAACCCUGGCUACUCCUCCAUCCCACCUGUUUUCCAGCUCUGUUUGAACUGGAAAGGGGAGAAAACCAACAGCAACGAUGACAACAUUCGGGCCAUGGAGGGCGAAGUCAAUGUGUGCUACAAGGAGCUGUGUGGCCCUUGGCCCAGCCACCAGCUGUUGACCAACCAGCUGCAGCGGCUGUGUGUGCUGCUGGAUGUUUACCUGGAGACCGAGAGCCAUGACGACAGUGUGGAGGGGCCCAAGGAAUUUCCCCAGGAGAAGAUGUGUCUGCGGCUCUUCAGGGGUCCUAGCAGGAUGAAGCCAUUUAAAUACAACCAUCCUCAGGGAUUCUUCAGCCAUCGCUGAUCUCCCGCGCAGACCGUUGUUUCCCCCAAGGCCUCACCCUGAGCACUGGGCUUCUGCUUUCUGCUCUGGCCCACAUGUGACUCUUGAUAUUCUCCAAAGACACCAGCCAAUUAAAAAGCGUCACCUGACCAGUGGCCUUUGUCUGUGGUUCCUGGCAAGGUGGCUUUGCAGUCUGGAAGGGCAGGUGGGAGCUGUGACACAGUGUGAAAAAGCAUUUGUAGAGAGACUUUUUCUCAGCAGCCAAUAAAAGCAGAGUGGAAAAAGAUUCCAAUUCUGCAGAGAGAUGCUCACCUCUUGUCUACGCACACCCUAUUUGUGCUUUGCGGGGUGAGGUCCUCAUGAUCUUGUAUUUAUUAUCCCAAGUUCCUGCUGUUAAGAGGUGGUAGGAGAAGCCAAAGGCAGCAGAGCACAAAAAGCAAAACUCUUCCCUCCCCACCCGCUCUUCCCAUUAGUCCUGUCAGGGUUGCCGAUGGACAAAUUGUCUCUGAUCGUUGGAUGUUAUAAAUGUCUGACAGUGCAGUGCAAACAGAAGACAAACUCAGUUGAUCCUUGAACAACUCAGGGGUUAGGGGCACCAACACCCCCUGCCCUGCACAGUUGAAAAAUCCGUGUAUAACUUUUGACUCCCUAAAAACUUAACUAAUAGCCUGCUGUUGACCAGUAGUAUGCUAUUAGUAGUUACUUACUGCUAACAUAGUCAGUACAUAUUUUCAGUAUAUAUUUUGUAUCUUAUACACUGUAUUCUUACAAUACAGUAAACUAGAGAAAAGAAAAUGUUAUAAGGAAAGUCACAAGGGGGCCUGAGUGCAGUGGCUCACGUCUGUAAUCCCAGCACUUUGGGAGGCCAAGGCGGGUGGAUCACUUGAGGUCAGGAGUUUGAGACCAGCCUGGCCGACAUGGUGAAACCCUGUCUCUACUAAAAACAUGGAAAUUAGCCAAGCGUGGUGGCGCAUGCCUGUAGUCCCAGUUACUCAGGAGGCUGAGGCAGAAUUACUUGAACCCAUGAGGCAGAGGUUGCAGUAAGCCAAGAUCACGCUCCUGCGCUCCGGCUUGGGCGAGAGUGAGACUCCGUCUCAAAAAUAAAUAAAUAAGAAAGCCAUAAGGAAGAAAAUAUAUAUCUACUAUUAAGUAGAAGUGGAUCACCAUAAAGGUCUUCACAUACUGUCUCAGGGUUGAAUAGUCUAAGGAAGAGGAGGGGUUGGUCUUGGUGUCUCAGGGAUGGCAGAGGCAGAAAAAGUGGGGGAGGUGGAGGGGGAGGCAGGCACCACUGUUAUUUUUAUUGAACAAAAUCUGUGCAGGGACUCAUGACUGUAAUCCUAGUACUUUGGAAAGCUAAGGCGGGAGGAUCCCUUGAGGCCAGGAGUUCAGGUCCAGCCUGGGCAACGUAGUGAGAGACCCUGUAUCUACAAAAAAUUUAAAAAUCAGCCAGGUGUGGUGGUAUGCACCAAUAGUCCCAGUUACUCAGAAGGCUGAGGUGGGCGGAUGACUGGAGUCCAGGAGUUCAAGGUAGCAGUGAGCUAUUCAUCGUGCCUGUACUGUACUCCAGCCUGGGAAACAAUGCGAGUCCCUAUCUCUAAAAAAUUUUAAAAAAAGAAAUCUGCAUAUAAUAGACCCACAGAGUCCAAACUAUUGUUCAGAGAUCAACUGUACUUCACAGAGAGUAAUUCUAAGUCUUACAGGAUUUCAUGGAGAUGGCGAGAGUGGUGUUGGAGAAUCAAUCACAUACAGAGAUACAGGACAGUGAGACCAGGUAACAUUUGAGGAGAAUAUUUUUUUUUUAUUGAGACAGGGUCUUGCUCUGUUGUCCAGGCUGGAGUGCAGUGGCACGAACACAGCUCACUGCCGCCUCAACCUCUCCUGGGUUCAAGUGAUCCUCCUGCCUCAGCCUCCCAAGUAGCUGGGACCACAGGUGUGUGCCACCAUUUCUGGCUAAUUUUUAAAUUUUUUGUAGAGGCGGGAUCCCACUAUUUUUCCCAGGCUGGUCUCAAACUCCUGGGCUCAAAUGAUCCUCCCACCUCGGCCUCCCAAAGUGCUAGGAUUAUAGGCAUGAGCCACCACACCCGGCCUGAGUAGAGUCUUUAAGGUAAUGACAAAAGUGCCUCAAAAUAUAAUUAUUUGAUUAAGAGAAGUCUUGGGAAGAUAGGUAACAACCUUUAAAAUGUUCAUAAAAUUACAUCCUUUGUAAUACUCCUGCAAGUCAAAGUAAAGGAUGGCAUAGACUAUUCUUGGACAGUUUUGUCAAAAAGUGUAUCUUGACCCCACCAUCAGUACUCCAUUCUUCAUUUUAAAAAAUAAGAUGGGCUGGGCACAGUGGCUUACGCCUUUAAUAUCAGUACUUUGGGAGGCUGGUGGGCGGAUCACCUGAGAUCAGGAGUUCAAGACCAGCCUGGCCAACAUGGUGAAACCCCGUCUCUACUAAAAAUACAAAAAUUAGCUGGGCAUGGUGGUGCGCGCCUGUAAUCCCAGCCACUCGGGAGGCUGAGGCAGGAGAAUUGCUUGAAUCCCCGAGGCGGAGGUUGCACUGAGCCGAGAUGGUGCCACUGCACCAUCUGGACAACAGAGCAAGACUCCGUCUUGG